CCAGGAUUGGAACGCACCCGAGCGGCUCUCGACAAGAGUUUGUGGGUGGGGGCGCCGAAGCCUUGGACGGGUCGUCUCGGCAGUGUUGCCCGAGGGAGUUGGGGUUGGCAAAGGGAAGUCAUGGAGGCAGUGGGAUCGAGGACUCCUAGGUCCGGCGCUCGCCACCCCCGUCGCCCGCCGCCUGCCUCCCUCCACGGGGCGAGUUCCAGGCUGGCCCGGAGGCCAGGAGGAUCUGGCACGUACUGGGGGAGGGGCUGGCCUGAGUUUUUUGCUGCGGGGCUGUGGGGUGUCUCCGAGUUUGGGGGAGAUUCCAUUUAGGGGAGAGGAACCGGCCUGGGCAGAGGGAGGGAUGCCCUCUGUCUGCGGGAGUCCCUCUCCUUCCCCUCACCCAAAACCUUGGGAAUGAAAGGGGUGGGGUCGGCUCCCCACAUCCCCCAAGGCCUGCCGCAGGGUGGGCAGGGGAGCUGACUUUAUUCAAAGCAGACUCUGGGGCUCGACUGAAAGGCUAGAGGUGGAAUCAGGCGUGGGAGCCUCUUUGCCCAUAUCCUCUCCUUACCAGAUUACCCCUGUGAGCUGGAGGGACCUGGUGGGGGUUGCAUAGUAAAGGGUGAUGUGGGAGCCCUCUGUAAUCUUUAGGGAGAGUGAGGACUGGGGAUGGGAGAAGGCGGCAGCGGGCACUGGACCGACAGAUACAGGCCCUGGGUAGGCUCCUCUACAUCUGGAAAGGCCCAGAAUUGAAGAAUUGAGGCCCAUGUCCGAGUAUGGUGGGUGGUGCUGGCACUGCUGGGCCCCGCCUGGGCAGUGCCUCUUACCAUGAACUUUCUGAAGUCGUUUUUAAUCCCCUGGAGCCUCCUUUUGCCAAGGAGGGCAGGGGCAGAUGGGCCCUGGGGAUGGGAUAGACAGGAGGUGGCCAGGAAGGCUUGGCAAGGCAGUGGGCAGAGCCAUCCUUAGGGCUGGGCCUUGGCCUUGGCUGGUUCCAAACUCUGGUCUCAGCCUGAUCAGGGUUUGGGAGGGACUUGAGGUCUGGGAGGCACUGAGCCUGGGCCUGCCAGGCUGAAUGGGACAUGGCUGUGGCUGUGGGAGCCGGUGGUAUGAAGAACAGCAGAUCUGUGAGAGUGCAAAUGGACCAACACUCAGGGGAGGAGAAGGUAGAGGCACAAGGCUUAGGAGCCUGACUCUGGGGAGGAGGGAGGUGGUCUGUGCUCCCAGGGCUCAUAGUGAUGGGUUGCUGGACAAAGUGGGUUGGGGGACCAUAUAGAGAAAUUUUGUGGCUUGGAACAGUGCUCUACCCUGUUUCCUGCCAUACCAGUCUGGCAUGGGGUGCCAGAAAUGUUGGGAGGCCGGCAAGUUCUGCGGGAUGGGCAGUGCCUGGAGUGGAGCCCAGGGUGGGAUGGUUGCAGUUGGUUGGACAAUUACAUAGCUCUGAAGCUAUCCCCUUGGGGGGGGUCAGAGUGUUCCUGGGAGGGUCAUGCAUUCUCCUGGAUAGCAUUUGCCCCUUUCUCUGUGAGUAUGAGCCAGAUGCUAGGAUGUGUUUCCAGGGGGCUUGGAACAUGGCCAGAAACUAGUCCUUUGGGAACAGGUCCGGGCCAGUGCUGGUGGGGGUGGUGUGUUGGGGGAGAUAAGAACAGGGAAGGGGACUGGUGAAUGGAGGAGGCUGAAGCAAAAUGUUGUGGGUGGUGGAUGGUGGUGGGAAACCUGCUCACUCUGGGCUCUGUCUCCAGCAGCUCUGGGGACUGACAGCCAAGGACACAGGGACUGAUAGAACCAGGCAUCUGACUGGCUAGAAAGACGUGUGUUCUUGCUCAUGAUUUCCUCAUCUUUCCAUCUCUUGACGAUGACAGAGGUUUGGGUUUAAAGUGUUGUAGAGUGAGGAGAAGAACUAAUAUUUUUCAAGUGUGUACUUCUUGACAGGCAUUAUUAGAUUCUUUCCUGAGGACCAUUAUCAUUUCCAUUUUGCAGAUGAAGGUACUGACACAGAGAGGUUAAAUAACUUGCCCAAGGCAGUGUGGCUAGCAAAUAAUCACGCUAAGGUUUGGAACCCUGGUCUCAUGCCAAAGAUCAUGCUUCUAAUGAAGUAUUUUGAAGAGCAAGGCUUUCUUUGGUGACCUUUUCCAAAUGCCAGCCUGACCAAAAGUCUUGUAUUCCUGAUCUGUCCUUCCAGAUGGUGCUGUUGGUGAUGUUAAGAGGUUGAAGGGGCCAGGCAUGGUGGCUCAUGCCUAUACUCCCAGCACUUUGGGAGGCCGAGACAGGCAGAUCACCUGAGGUUAGGAGUUCGAGACCAGCCUGGCCAACAUGGUUAAACCCUGUCUGUACUAAAAAUACAAAAUUUAGCCGGGUGUGGUGGUAGGUGCUUGUAAUCUCAGCUAUGGGGAAGCCGAGGCAGAAUUGCUUGAACCCAGGAGGCAGAGGUUGCAGUGAGCUGAGAUUGUGCCACUGCACUCCAGCCUAGGUGGGGCAGAGUGAGACUCCGUCUUAAACCAAAAAACAAAAGGAGGUUGAAGGACGUGCUGCUCUGUGGGAUAUAGGAGAAGGGGUGCUGACAGAUCUUGGCUGAGGGUGACUCAGGGAUGGGAGGUUUGGGGUAUGCAGAGAAUUCCCCAGCCUGCCUUCUGCGUGUGGGUCCCUGGGUGUCUGCUUCAAGCGCUGCCCAUCUGGCUUGAGCUCUCAUUCUAUGGCCACCUGGGGCAAGUGCUGAGUAUUCCUCCAUCCUGUCCCCGAGUGAGUACAAAUGUCAGUGCUGCUAGCUCAGCAGGUUUAAUUACAAGGGACCCCUCAGGGUACUCUGUGAGCAUAGAGGAGUGUGGCCCUGGUGGGGACACAGGCAUGCAUGGAUGACAGUGCUGUCAGCCUCAUCUUAUUCUGACCUGGGCUCAGCCAGGAGUCACAUUAAAGGUAUCAUCAUGGAGUCCUCCCACCUCAGUUCAUGACAUUUCCUCCAGGAAAUGUGGGAUCUGGGACUGAUUUGGUUACCAUGAUCUCUAUAACUUGGGCCAGCCAUAUAAAACUGCCAUGGACCUCAGUUUUUGUUUAUAUAUAUUUUUCCUUUCAAAUUUGUCUUGUGCCCCAGGGGGCAACAGGACCAGUUUCUCAGGGUUUUGGUGAAGAUCAGAUGGAAUUAGGGAUGUGAAAAGAUCUUGAACAGUUUAAAGCAUAGAGAAAGUGCAUGGAGUAUCAUUCGUCCAUCCAUCCAGUCAUCCAUCUACUCAAUGAACAUUUAUUAUUAUUAUUUUAUUUUUUGAGAUGGAGUUUCGCUCUUAUUGCCCAAGCUGGAGCGCAAUGGUGUGAUCUCAGCUCACUGCAACCUCUGCCUCCUGGAUUUAAGUGAUUCUCUCACCUCAGCCUCCCGAAUAGCUGGGAUUACAGGCAUGCGCCACCAUGCCUGGCUAAUUUUGUGUUUUUAGUAGAAAUGGGGUUUCACCAUGUUGGUCCGGCUGGUCUCGAACUCCUGACCUCAGGUGAUCCACUCACCUCGGCUUCCCAAAGUGCUGGGAUUACAAGUGUGGGCCACCAUACCUGGCCUCAAUGAACACUUGUUUAGGUCCUUCUAAGGGUUGUGGAUACAGCAGUGAGCACAGCAGGUCAAAAUCCUUGCCUUCAUAAGGCUGACAUUCCAGUCAGGAGAGACAGAAAAUGAACACAUAAGAAAAAUAUAUAGAAUGGCAGUUGCUGAUUAGAGCUAUGGAGAAAAAGCAUAAAGCUGGGAAAAAGAUAGAGAGCUCCAGGAAAGGGGGUUGCUAUUUUAAUAGGGUGGUCAGAGGGAGCCUCACUGAUAAGGGGACAUUUGGGAUGUGACCUGGAGGAGCUCUUGUUCCAGACAGAGGGAACAGCAGGCACUGAGGUCCCAGGCUGGCCUGUGCGGGGUGUGUUGGGAAACAGCAAAGAGGUUCUUGUGACUGGGGUGCAGUGAGGAAGCUGAAGAGCCUUAGGAUUAUCACUGUUAGCUGGUGGCAGAUCAUGAGGUCAGGAGAUCGAGACCAUCCUAGCUAACACAGUGAAACUCCGUCUCUACUAAAAAAUAGAAAAAAUUUCCCUGGGCAUGGUGGCAGGCGCCUGUAGUCCCAGCUAUUUGGGAGGCUGAAUGGUGUGAACCCGGGAGGCGGAGCUUGCAGUGAGCCAAGAUCGUGCCACUGCACUCCAGCCUGGGUGACAGAGUGAGACUCCGUCUCAAAAAAAAAAAAAAAAAAAAAAAAACUCCAGAUUUUUUCUUCUGCUUCUGUUGAGAAAAAUCAGAUCGGGACCCACUGGGACCCAGUGGCAACAGUCUACAGCUGCUGGGUGGUGCCUGCCCCAUGCACAGGCAACAUGUCAUGGUUUAGUGGCCUCCUGGUCCCUAAAGUGGAUGAACGGAAAACAGCCUGGGGUGAACGCAAUGGGCAGAAGCGUUCGCGGCGCCGUGGCACUCGGGCAGGUGGCUUCUGCACGCCCCGCUAUAUGAGCUGCCUCCGGGAUGCAGAGCCACCCAGCCCCACCCCUGCGGGCCCCCCUCGGUGCCCCUGGCAGGAUGACGCCUUCAUCCGGAGGGGCGGCCCAGGCAAGGGCAAGGAGCUGGGGCUGCGGGCAGUGGCCCUGGGCUUCGAGGAUACCGAGGUGACAACGACAGCGGGCGGGACGGCUGAGGUGGCGCCCGACGCGGUGCCCAGGAGUGGGCGAUCCUGCUGGCGCCGUCUGGUGCAGGUGUUCCAGUCGAAGCAGUUCCGUUCGGCCAAGCUGGAGCGCCUGUACCAGCGGUACUUCUUCCAGAUGAACCAGAGCAGCCUGACGCUGCUGAUGGCGGUGCUGGUGCUGCUCACAGCGGUGCUGCUGGCUUUCCACGCCGCACCCGCCCGCCCUCAGCCUGCCUAUGUGGCACUGUUGGCCUGUGCCGCCGCCCUGUUCGUGGGGCUCAUGGUGGUGUGUAACCGGCAUAGCUUCCGCCAGGACUCCAUGUGGGUGGUGAGCUACGUGGUGCUGGGCAUCCUGGCGGCAGUGCAGGUCGGGGGCGCUCUCGCAGCAGACCCGCGCAGCCCCUCUGCGGGCCUCUGGUGCCCUGUGUUCUUUGUCUACAUCGCCUACACGCUCCUCCCCAUCCGCAUGCGGGCUGCCGUCCUCAGCGGCCUGGGCCUCUCCACCUUGCAUUUGAUCUUGGCCUGGCAACUUAACCGUGGUGAUGCCUUCCUCUGGAAGCAGCUCGGUGCCAAUGUGCUGCUGUUCCUCUGCACCAACGUCAUUGGCAUCUGCACACACUAUCCAGCAGAGGUGUCUCAGCGCCAGGCCUUUCAGGAGACCCGCGGUUACAUCCAGGCCCGGCUCCACCUGCAGCAUGAGAAUCGGCAGCAGGAGCGGCUGCUGCUGUCGGUAUUGCCCCAGCACGUUGCCAUGGAGAUGAAAGAAGACAUCAACACAAAAAAAGAAGACAUGAUGUUCCACAAGAUCUACAUACAGAAGCAUGACAAUGUCAGCAUCCUGUUUGCAGACAUUGAGGGCUUCACCAGCCUGGCAUCCCAGUGCACUGCGCAGGAGCUGGUCAUGACCCUGAAUGAGCUCUUUGCCCGGUUUGACAAGCUGGCUGCGGAGAAUCACUGCCUGAGGAUCAAGAUCUUGGGGGACUGUUACUACUGUGUGUCAGGGCUGCCGGAGGCCCGGGCCGACCAUGCCCACUGCUGUGUGGAGAUGGGGGUAGACAUGAUUGAGGCCAUCUCGCUGGUACGUGAGGUGACAGGUGUGAAUGUGAACAUGCGCGUGGGCAUCCACAGCGGGCGCGUGCACUGCGGCGUCCUUGGCUUGCGGAAAUGGCAGUUCGAUGUGUGGUCCAAUGAUGUGACCCUGGCCAACCACAUGGAGGCAGGAGGCCGGGCUGGCCGCAUCCACAUCACUCGGGCAACACUGCAGUACCUGAACGGGGACUACGAGGUGGAGCCAGGCCGUGGUGGCGAGCGCAACGCGUACCUCAAGGAGCAGCACAUUGAGACUUUCCUCAUCCUGGGCGCCAGCCAGAAACGGAAAGAGGAGAAGGCCAUGCUGGCCAAGCUGCAGCGGACUCGGGCCAACUCCAUGGAAGGGCUGAUGCCGCGCUGGGUUCCUGAUCGUGCCUUCUCCCGGACCAAGGACUCCAAGGCCUUCCGCCAGAUGGGCAUUGAUGAUUCCAGCAAAGACAACCGGGGCACCCAAGAUGCCCUGAACCCUGAGGAUGAGGUGGAUGAGUUCCUGAGCCGUGCCAUCGAUGCCCGCAGCAUUGAUCAGCUGCGGAAGGACCAUGUGCGCCGGUUUCUGCUCACCUUCCAGAGAGAGGAUCUUGAGAAGAAGUACUCCCGGAAGGUGGAUCCCCGCUUCGGAGCCUACGUUGCCUGUGCCCUGUUGGUCUUCUGCUUCAUCUGCUUCAUCCAGCUUCUCAUCUUCCCACACUCCACCCUGAUGCUUGGGAUCUAUGCCAGCAUCUUCCUGCUGCUGCUAAUCACCGUGCUGAUCUGUGCUGUGUACUCCUGUGGUUCUCUGUUCCCUAAGGCCCUGCAACGUCUGUCCCGCAGCAUUGUCCGCUCACGGGCACAUAGCACCGCAGUUGGCAUCUUUUCCGUCCUGCUUGUGUUUACUUCUGCCAUUGCCAACAUGUUCACCUGUAACCACACCCCCAUACGGAGCUGUGCAGCCCGGAUGCUGAAUUUAACACCUGCUGACAUCACUGCCUGCCACCUGCAGCAGCUCAAUUACUCUCUGGGCCUGGAUGCUCCCCUGUGUGAGGGCACCAUGCCCACCUGCAGCUUUCCUGAGUACUUCAUCGGGAACAUGCUGCUGAGUCUCUUGGCCAGCUCUGUCUUCCUGCACAUCAGCAGCAUCGGGAAGUUGGCCAUGAUCUUUGUCUUGGGGCUCAUCUAUUUGGUGCUGCUUCUGCUGGGUCCCCCAGCCACCAUCUUUGACAACUAUGACCUACUGCUUGGCGUCCAUGGCUUGGCUUCUUCCAAUGAGACCUUUGAUGGGCUGGACUGUCCAGCUGCAGGGAGGGUGGCCCUCAAAUAUAUGACCCCUGUGAUUCUGCUGGUGUUUGCGCUGGCGCUGUAUCUGCAUGCUCAGCAGGUGGAGUCGACUGCCCGCCUAGACUUCCUCUGGAAACUACAGGCAACAGGGGAGAAGGAGGAGAUGGAGGAGCUACAGGCAUACAACCGGAGGCUGCUGCAUAACAUUCUGCCCAAGGACGUGGCGGCCCACUUCCUGGCCCGGGAGCGCCGCAAUGAUGAACUCUACUAUCAGUCGUGUGAGUGUGUGGCUGUUAUGUUUGCCUCCAUUGCCAACUUCUCUGAGUUCUAUGUGGAGCUGGAGGCAAACAAUGAGGGUGUCGAGUGCCUGCGGCUGCUCAACGAGAUCAUCGCUGACUUUGAUGAGAUUAUCAGCGAGGAGCGGUUCCGGCAGCUGGAAAAGAUCAAGACGAUUGGUAGCACCUACAUGGCUGCCUCAGGGCUGAACGCCAGCACCUACGAUCAGGUGGGCCGCUCCCACAUCACUGCCCUGGCUGACUACGCCAUGCGGCUCAUGGAGCAGAUGAAGCACAUCAAUGAGCACUCCUUCAACAAUUUCCAGAUGAAGAUUGGGCUGAACAUGGGCCCAGUCGUGGCAGGUGUCAUCGGGGCUCGGAAGCCACAGUAUGACAUCUGGGGGAACACAGUGAAUGUCUCUAGUCGUAUGGACAGCACGGGGGUCCCCGACCGAAUCCAGGUGACCACGGACCUGUACCAGGUUCUAGCUGCCAAGGGCUACCAGCUGGAGUGUCGAGGGGUGGUCAAGGUGAAGGGCAAGGGGGAGAUGACCACCUACUUCCUCAAUGGGGGCCCCAGCAGUUAACAGGGCCCAGCCACAAAUUCAGCUGAAGGGACCAAGGUGGGCAUUGAGUGGACUCUGUGCUCACUGGGUGGAGCUGUGGCAGGGGGCACUGAGCCUCCAGACCCUGCUAACCACAAAAGGGAACAUCCCAGCAGGCUGUGCUUGGAUCAUGCUCGUCUGCCCUCAAGCUGGAAAACAAGGGGCUACCUACCGAGAGGAUUAUGCAAGUGACUUUCUUUCUUACUUGGGGUAGGGCUGUUCCCUCUCCAAUCUUCCAGCCUUUGGGAGCAGGGGAGGGGUCAGUAGCAGAAGCAGAGGGAGGCCUCUUGCCUGAGGGAUUAAAAUGGCAGCUUGCCAUGCCUACCCUUCCCUGUCUGUCUGGGCAGCAGGUUCAGGGCUGAGCCCUUCUUUUCCCUCUUUUUUCCUGGGAAUAUUUUGUACAAUAUUUUGUACAAAGACAGGCAUGAGGAGUGCCUAUUCCAUGCUUGCCUUUGCAAUACCUGCAUCCCCAGCACUGGUCCUGGGCACUUCCCCACCCCAGCCAGGUGUCCCUCCUAUGCACAGAGCAGAGGAGGGAGAAGCUCUGGGGAGCCAGCUUUGGCCAUAUUUCAGGAGAAUGUUUCCAUGUGCCAAAUCUUAGUCCCAUGAUCUGUCCCCAAAGGGGAACAAAGGGACCUCUGACAGCUUAGAUUUAGCCCCAGUUCCUGCACGCUCCAGGGAACGGGGUGUCUGGCCUCACUGGUACUGUGAAAAAUGCUCAGAGAGCAAGCCUGUGUGUGGGGAUGUCAGGUCAGGAGCUGGAAGUUCACCUGCAGGUGCCAAAGAGCAGGCCGGCCAGGGCUGGGGCAGUGCCAGACUCUGAUCUGAGGACCCCGUCGGGGUCCAGAUCAGGUCACUCUGCCCCAGUGCUCUCUUGCUGUCUGCUGACAAGGGGGCAUGGAGCAUCUCUUCCUCUUCUGUUGCCAAAUAGAAAAGGGUCAGGGCAUGGAGAAAGGUGACCCUGAUCCCAAACCUGCCCUCCCAAGUCUCUGGUGUUGGGGAGGGCCCGUGUGUUUGUGUAACUGUGUGUGCAUGUUGGUCUUUGUGUGCAUAUCUGUUUUCCAGGUCUAUGUGAGUCCUUGUGCUCCUGCUCCUCAGCUCUCCACCCCAGGUUGCCUCUCUCCUGUGGGCCUCUGUCUUCUGGGAAUAAAGCAGGGUUUCCUACUUCAGGGGAUGUAGAGAGAUGCCCAGGUUGCACAGGAGUGGGAUGGGGUGUGGUAGCAAAAGGAGGGAGAGGAGUCCUUUUUGUGCCAAAUCCCUAAGUGCCGUUCGGGGGCCAUGUGUGCAGCAUGACUCUCCCUGUCUGUGGCAGGGACCCAAGCGCUUGCUUAAGCCCCAGUGCUCCAUGCCAGCACUUGAACUGUCUGGGGUUUGAUGGACAGAGGCUGAGGAAUUUCCUGGCUUCCCCAGAUAGUGUCCUGGGACAUGGUAUGCUUUGGGGCUGGGGUAGCAUGGAAUCCCUCUGAGGACCUGGAUACUGGUACUACGGGGUGGGGAAGAGGAACCUUAAACUUGGCUUUCCCCAGCCUUCAGCCUGAGUCUAGCAUGUUUCUAGCUCCCCAGUCCCUUGUGAAGCCUUGAGGGCUGGCAGAAGGGUUAGGAGGUUGAACUCUAGAUUCCCUUCCUGUCUUUGCCUUCCUUUUACCCCUUUCCCUGCAACCUCCUUGACUCUGGCCUGAAUUUGUUGGUGCCUCAGUUUCUCUGUCUGUACCUAUUUAAGCCAAAGGCACUAGCCUGAAUUUUGCUUGAAGAUCACUUUGUCUUGGAAAUGACUAGAGAGGCAGAGGAGAAGGGUUUCCAGAGUUGCUAGGUUUGGGAGUGGAAGGGGCAGGCAGUGCACUUGCCCCUCCUCAUGCCCCUUCUGACACCAGCUCCCUGUGGAGGCCUGGUUUCUGGGUAAUGCCUCCCUUGGGCAUCUUCAUGCAUCAACCAAAUGGGCCAUCAGGUACUUCAUUAGUCAUGGCAGAAGGAGGGGAAAAGACUUGUUUUCCAGACAGAAAAUCUACUCCCCUGUCCCCAGCCAUAUCCCUGGAUAGGAAGGGAUAGGAAGAGACUACUUGGUGCCAUGGGGUAGGGGUGAGGGUAUAAGUAGAUCAGAGUGGGAAGACCUCAGCCUUGGGUGGCUUGUCUCUGCUUCUUGCCAGGUGGGAGGGCCUGUCCACACCCUGGAUCCCCGUACCACAGUGCCAGCCAUGCCCUUCCCCUGGGCUACCAUUGUCCCUUUCCUCACCCAGUUGGUAGAGGAGUCAGGAGGUGGGAGGCCGUGGGCUUUGGUUUUAUAAUGUAACCACUGUGGGGGUGGGGGAGGAUGGUGAACCAUGUAUUUCAGUGAAAUAUUUAAUAUAUUUAAAUAUCAAUAAAAUCAAACUCUUUGUAAAA